GGCCAGCGCAUGGGCCCUGUGUCUGUCGUCGGGGUGACAGCUGCAGAGGAAGAGACCCCCAGCCCCACAGAACCCAGCAUGGAGGCCCCGGAGCCCGCUGAGGAGCCGCUCCUGGGGGAGCUAACAGUGACAGGAUCCUCCCCUGACUCGCUGAGCCUCUCCUGGACCGUCCCCCAGGGCCGCUUCGACUCCUUCACCGUGCAGUACAAGGACAGGGACGGGCGGCCCCAGGUGGUGCGUGUUGGGGGCGAGGAGAGUGAAGUCACCGUGGGGGGCCUGGAGCCUGGGCGCAAGUACAAGAUGCACCUGUACGGCCUCCACGAGGGGCGGCGCGUGGGCCCAGUGUCUGCUGUGGGCGUCACGGCCCCCGAAGAGGAGUCCCCUGAUGCUCCUCUUGCAAAGCUGCGCCUAGGGCAGAUGACAGUGAGAGACAUCACCUCCGACUCCCUCAGCCUCUCCUGGACAGUCCCCGAGGGCCAGUUUGACCAUUUCUUGGUCCAGUUUAAGAAUGGGGAUGGGCAGCCCAAGGCGGUGCGGGUGCCGGGACACGAGGAUGGGGUCACCAUCUCGGGCCUGGAGCCAGACCACAAGUACAAGAUGAACCUGUACGGCUUCCACGGUGGCCAGCGCGUGGGCCCCGUGUCUGCUGUUGGUUUAACUGCCCCAGGAAAGGAUGAAGAAAUGGCCCCAGCCUCGACAGAACCUCCCACCCCUGAACCCCCCAUCAAGCCUCGCCUGGAGGAGCUGACCGUGACAGAUGCGACCCCUGACUCCCUCAGCCUGUCCUGGACGGUUCCCGAGGGACAGUUUGACCACUUCCUGGUCCAGUACAAGAAUGGGGAUGGGCAGCCCAAGGCAACACGGGUGCCAGGACAUGAGGACAGGGUCACCAUCUCCGGCCUGGAGCCAGACAACAAGUACAAGAUGAACCUGUACGGCUUCCACGGUGGCCAGCGUGUGGGCCCCGUGUCUGCCAUCGGGGUGACAGCUGCAGAGGAAGAGACCCCCAGCCCCACAGAACCCAGCAUGGAGGCCCCGGAGCCCCCUGAGGAGCCGCUCCUGGGGGAGCUGACAGUGACAGGAUCCUCCCCUGACUCGCUGAGCCUCUCCUGGACCGUCCCCCAGGGCCGCUUCGACUCCUUCACCGUGCAGUACAAGGACAGGGACGGGCGGCCCCAGGUGGUGCGUGUUGGGGGCGAGGAGAGCGAGGUCACCGUGGGGGGCCUGGAGCCUGGGCGCAAAUACAAGAUGCACCUGUACGGCCUCCACGAGGGGCGGCGCGUGGGCCCGGUGUCCACCGUGGGCGUGACUGCCCCACAAGAGGAUGUGGACGAGACCCCCAGCCCUACAGAACCAGGCACAGAGGCCCCAGAGCCCCCCGAGGAGCCUCUCCUGGGGGAGCUGACAGUGACAGGAUCCUCCCCUGACUCGCUGAGCCUUUCCUGGACCGUCCCCCAGGGCCGCUUUGACUCCUUCACCGUGCAGUACAAGGACAGGGACGGGCGGCCCCAGGCGGUGCGUGUUGGGGGCCAGGAGAGCAAGGUCACUGUGAGGGGCCUGGAGCCUGGGCGCAAGUACAAGAUGCACCUGUACGGCCUCCACGAGGGGCGGCGCCUGGGCCCGGUGUCUGCCGUGGGCGUCACAGAGGAUGAAGCCGAGACCACCCAAGCAGUGCCUACCAUGACCCCUGAGCCCCCCAUCAAGCCUCGCCUGGGGGAGCUGACCAUGACAGAUGCCACCCCUGACUCCCUCAGCCUGUCCUGGACGGUUCCCGAGGGCCAGUUUGACCACUUCCUGGUCCAGUACAGGAAUGGGGAUGGGCAGCCCAAGGCGGUGCGGGUGCCGGGGCACGAGGACGGGGUCACCAUCUCAGGCCUGGAGCCAGACCAUAAAUACAAGAUGAACCUGUACGGCUUCCACGGUGGCCAGCGCGUGGGCCCCAUCUCUGUCACUGGGGUGACGGCUGCAGAGGAAGAGACCCCCAGCCCCACGGAACUCAGCACUGAGGCCCCGGAGCCCCCUGAGGAGCCGCUCCUGGGGGAGCUGACAGUGACAGGAUCCUCCCCUGACUCGCUGAGCCUCUCCUGGACCAUCCCCCAGGGCCACUUCGACUCCUUCACCGUGCAGUACAAGGACAGGGACGGGCGGCCCCAGGUGAUGCGUGUCAGGGGCGAGGAGAGCGAGGUCACCGUGGGGGGCCUGGAGCCCGGGCGCAAAUACAAGAUGCACCUGUACGGCCUCCACGAGGGGCGGCGUGUGGGCCCGGUGUCCACCGUGGGUGUGACAGCUCCAGAGGAUGAAGCAGAGACCACCCAAGCAGUGCCCACCACAACCCCUGAGCCCCCCAACAAGCCUCGCCUCGGGGAGCUGACCGUGACAGAUGCCACCCCUGACUCCCUCAGCCUGUCCUGGAUGGUCCCCGAGGGCCAGUUUGACCACUUCCUGGUCCAGUACAGGAAUGGGGAUGGGCAGCCCAAGGUGGUGCGGGUGCCGGGGCACGAGGACGGGGUCACCAUCUCAGGCCUGGAGCCAGACCACAAGUACAAGAUGAACCUGUACGGCUUCCACGGUGGCCAGCGCGUGGGCCCCAUCUCUGUCAUUGGGGUGACAGCUGCAGAGGAAGAAACUCCCGCCCCCACAGAACCCAGCACGGAGGCCCCGGAGCCCCCUGAGGAGCCGCUCCUGGGGGAGCUGACAGUGACAGGAUCCUCCCCUGACUCGCUGAGCCUCUCCUGGACCAUCCCCCAGGGCCGCUUCGACUCCUUCACUGUGCAGUACAAGGACAGGGACGGGCGGCCCCAGGUGGUGCGUGUCAGGGGCGAGGAGAGCGAGGUCACCGUGGGGGGCCUGGAGCCCGGGUGCAAAUACAAGAUGCACCUGUACGGCCUCCACGAGGGGCAGCGCGUGGGCCCAGUGUCCGCUGUGGGUGUGACAGCUCCAAAGGAUGAAGCCGAGACCACCCAAGCAGUGCCUACCAUGACCCCUGAGCCCCCCAUCAAGCCUCGCCUGGGGGAGCUGACCGUGACAGAUGCCACCCCCGACUCCCUCAGCCUGUCCUGGAUGGUUCCCGAGGGCCAGUUUGACCACUUCCUGGUCCAGUACAGGAAUGGGGAUGGGCAGCCCAAGGCGGUGCGGGUGCCGGGGCACGAGGACGGGGUCACCAUCUCAGGCCUGGAGCCAGACCAUAAAUACAAGAUGAACCUGUACGGCUUCCACGGUGGCCAGCGCGUAGGCCCUGUGUCUGCCAUUGGGGUGACGGAGGAAGAGACCCCCAGCCCCACAGAACCCAGCACUGAGGCCCCGGAGGCCCCUGAGGAGCCGCUCCUGGGGGAGUUGACAGUGACAGGAUCCUCCCCUGACUCGCUGAGCCUCUCCUGGACCGUCCCCCAGGGCCGCUUCGACUCCUUCACCGUGCAGUACAAGGACAGGGACGGGCAGCCCCAGGUGGUGCGUGUCAGGGGCGAGGAGAGCGAGGUCACCGUGGGGGGCCUGGAGCCCGGGCGCAAAUACAAGAUGCAUCUGUACGGCCUCCACGAGGGGCAGCGCGUGGGCCCAGUGUCCACCGUGGGCAUCACGGCGCCCCUGCCCACACCACUGCCGGUGGAGCCCCGCCUGGGGGAGCUGGCGGUGGCGGCCGUGACCUCGGACUCAGUGGGCCUCUCAUGGACGGUGGCCCAGGGCCCCUUUGACUCCUUCCUGGUACAGUACAGGGACGCGCAGGGGCAGCCCCAGGCAGUGCCUGUGAGCGGAGACCUCCGAGCGGUCGCCGUCUCGGGGCUGGACCCGGCCCGCAAGUACAAGUUCCUGCUCUUUGGACUCCAGAAUGGGAAACGCCACGGCCCAGUCCCUGUGGAGGCCAGGACCGCCCCAGACACCAAACCGUCUCCCCGCCUGGGGGAGCUGACUGUGACAGAUGCGACCCCUGACUCCGUGGGCCUCUCGUGGACGGUCCCUGAGGGCGAAUUCGACUCCUUCGUGGUCCAGUACAAGGAUAAGGAUGGUCGGCUCCAGGUGGUGCCGGUGGCAGCCAACCAGCGGGAGGUCACAGUCCAGGGCCUGGAGCCCAGUAGGAAAUACAGGUUCCUGCUCUAUGGUCUGUCAGGCAGGAAACGACUGGGCCCCAUCUCUGCUGACAGCACCACAGCUCCCCUGGAGAAGGAGCUACCUCCCCACCUGGGGGAACUGACCGUGGCUGAGGAGACCUCCAGCUCUCUGCGCCUGUCCUGGACGGUAGCCCAGGGCCCCUUUGACUCCUUCGUGGUCCAGUACAGGGACACGGACGGGCAGCCCAGGGCAGUGCCUGUGGCCGCAGACCAGCGCACAGUCACCGUAGAGGACCUGGAGCCUGGCAAGAAAUACAAGUUUCUGCUCUACGGGCUCCUUGGGGGAAAGCGCCUGGGCCCGGUCUCUGCCCUGGGAAUGACAGCCCCAGAAGAGGACACACCAGCCCCAGAGUUAGCCCCAGAGGCCCCUGAGCCUCCUGAAGAGCCCCGCCUAGGAGUGCUGACCGUGACCGACACAACCCCAGACUCCAUGCGCCUCUCGUGGAGCGUGGCCCAGGGCCCCUUUGAUUCCUUCGUGGUCCAGUAUGAGGACACGAACGGGCAGCCCCAGGCCUUGCUCGUGGACGGCGACCAGAGCAAGAUCCUCAUCUCAGGCCUGGAGCCCAGCACCCCCUACAGGUUCCUCCUCUAUGGCCUCCAUGAAGGGAAGCGCCUGGGGCCCCUCUCAGCUGAGGGCACCACAGGGCUGGCUCCUGCUGGUCAGACCUCAGAGGAGUCAAGGCCCCGCCUGUCCCAGCUGUCUGUGACUGACGUGACCACCAGUUCACUGAGGCUCAACUGGGAGGCCCCACCGGGGGCCUUCGACUCCUUCCUGCUCCGCUUUGGGGUUCCAUCACCAAGCACACUGGAGCCGCAUCCGCGUCCACUGCUGCAGCGCGAGCUGAUGGUGCCGGGGACGCGGCACUCGGCCGUGCUCCGGGACCUGCGUUCCGGGACUCUGUACAGCCUGACACUGUAUGGGCUGCGAGGACCCCACAAGGCCGACAGCAUCCAGGGAACCGCCCGCACCCUCAGCCCAGUUCUGGAGAGCCCCCGUGACCUCCAAUUCAGUGAAAUCAGGGAGACCUCAGCCAAGGUCAACUGGAUGCCCCCACCAUCCCGGGCGGACAGCUUCAAAGUCUCCUACCAGCUGGCGGACGGAGGGGAGCCUCAGAGUGUGCAGGUGGAUGGCCAGGCCCGGACCCAGAAACUCCAGGGGCUGAUCCCAGGCGCUCGCUAUGAGGUGACCGUGGUCUCGGUCCGAGGCUUUGAGGAGAGUGAGCCUCUCACAGGCUUCCUCACCACGGUUCCUGACGGUCCCACACAGUUGCGUGCACUGAACUUGACCGAGGGAUUCGCCGUGCUGCACUGGAAGCCCCCCCAGAAUCCUGUAGACACCUAUGACAUCCAGGUCACAGCCCCUGGGGCCCCGCCUCUGCAGGCGGAGACCCCAGGCAGCGCGGUGGACUACCCCCUGCAUGACCUUGUCCUCCACACCAACUACACCGCCACAGUGCGUGGCCUGCGGGGCCCCAACCUCACUUCCCCAGCCAGCAUCACCUUCACCACAGGGCUAGAGGCCCCUCGGGACUUGGAGGCCAAGGAAGUGACCCCCCGCACCGCCCUGCUCACUUGGACUGAGCCCCCAGUCCGGCCCGCAGGCUACCUGCUCAGCUUCCACACCCCUGGUGGACAGACCCAGGAGAUCCUGCUCCCAGGAGGGAUCACAUCUCACCAGCUCCUUGGCCUCUUUCCCUCCACCUCCUACAAUGCACGGCUCCAGGCCAUGUGGGGCCAGAGCCUCCUGCCGCCCGUGUCCACCUCUUUCACCACGGGUGGGCUGCGGAUCCCCUUCCCCAGGGACUGCGGGGAGGAGAUGCAGAACGGAGCCGGUGCCUCCAGGACCAGCACCAUCUUCCUCAACGGCAACCGCGAGCGGCCCCUGAUCGUGUUUUGCGACAUGGAGACUGAUGGGGGCGGCUGGCUGGUGUUCCAGCGCCGCAUGGAUGGACAGACAGACUUCUGGAGGGACUGGGAGGACUAUGCCCAUGGUUUUGGGAACAUCUCUGGAGAGUUCUGGCUGGGCAAUGAGGCCCUGCACAGCCUGACACAGGCAGGUGACUACUCCAUGCGCGUGGACCUGCGGGCUGGGGACGAGGCUGUGUUCGCCCAGUACGACUCCUUCCACGUAGACUCGGCUGCGGAGUACUACCGCCUCCACUUGGAGGGCUACCACGGCACCGCAGGGGACUCCAUGAGCUACCACAGCGGCAGUGUCUUCUCUGCCCGUGAUCGGGACCCCAACAGCUUGCUCAUCUCCUGCGCUGUCUCCUACCGAGGGGCCUGGUGGUACAGGAACUGCCACUACGCCAACCUCAACGGGCUCUACGGGAGCACAGUGGACCAUCAGGGAGUGAGCUGGUACCACUGGAAGGGCUUCGAGUUCUCGGUGCCCUUCACGGAAAUGAAGCUGAGACCAAGAAACUUUCGCUCCCCAGCGGGGGGAGGCUGAGCUGCUGCCCACCUCUCUCGCACCCCAGUAUGACUGCCGAGCACUGAGGGGUCGCCCCGAGAGAAGAGCCAGGGUCCUUCACCACCCAGCCGCUGGAGGAAGCCUUCUCUGCCAGCGAUCUCGCAGCACUGUGUUUACAGGGGGGAGGGGAGGGGUUCGUACGGGAGCAAUAAAGGAGAAACUGAGGUACCCGGCU